AGAUCCUGUAACAUAAGAGGCAGGAAAAUAAAUAGCAGGGACUUGCAGAAUGGCUAAGGUAAGAAAGAAAAUGAACAAAGGAGCAGGGCCCAUUUCAGGGGCCUGUUUGUGUGUGCUAGCCCACCAGAUAAUAAGAUUACCCAUUUCUUAUCUCCGCCUCAAAUGGCCUCAGUGCCAGCCCCGUCCCGGAGCAGCGUCACAGUGCACGGGUGUCCUUCCGUCCUUCCCUCUCCUGCUGCCUGUCCUUAAUGACAGUCACAAGAGCAACAACAACAGCUGGCUUCGGGGAUGUCACAGCACCUGGGACUCACCUACCCUGACUUUGUAGUGCCUCUCGGCAGAGGCUACAUUCUUGAAAUCUAAAUGUUUAACGUCUGCUCUUGAGUGUGACUUCACCCCUCCCUUGACUCAAGCCUAGAUAGGGACCCAGGAUGUGCAUCUCUGGGAGCAGUUUGGAGGGACCUGGCCUCACUUCGGGCCUGACCUUUGGAAAUUCACCCAAAGCAGCCUGUUUGUUCCUGGCUCUGCCUCUGUUGUUGCUCUGACCUUUGACAAGUCAUUCCCUUGCCUAUGUCUCGGUUGCCCCAUCUGAGUGAGAGGUUGGGCUAAAAGGUCGCUAAGAUCACUUCUAGCCUGAUCUUCCAUGGCUCUAUAGUUCUCUUUGUUAUCUUUGGCCACUUACAUGUUUGCCAUAAUGAUUGCCAAUCAAACUGGGAAUGUUUAGCAGAUUUUAGACACUCAGACUGGAAAAUACAGACAAGGCCAUAGAAGUUAGUGUUGUCCUAGGGACGGCUCCUGGUUCACGCAUGCUCCUCAUACGGUCCCUAUUCUCAGCCUCCCAGCAGGGGCCUGGGUCUGAGGCCCCUAAGACCCCACGCUUAGGACAGGAAGGAAGUGGCCAGUGGCAGGCACCCAAGAAACUGUGUGGCUCAACGCUGUUCCAGUCCUGUUGUGUAACAAACCACCCCAAACCUGGAGGUGUAAGCAACCGUCUUACUACUCUCACAGAUUCUGUAGGUCAGGACUUCAGACAGAACACAGUGGGGAGAGCUUGUCUUCAGUGUCUAGGACCUCAGCUGGGAACACUCACAGGUUGGGUGGUCCACCUGCAGGGGCUGGAGAUCCUCCAAAGCAUCUUCACUCAGAUGGCUGGCAGUAAUGCUGCCCGAUGGGACCUCUACCGGGCUUUCUGCUCAUACAGAAGCUCAGGGCCAUGAGGAGGGGUCCCAGCUAACAGGUAGGAGCUGUGCUGCCUUUGAGGACUUAGCCUCAGAAGCACACCUGUGCUCCAUUCUAUUAGUUACAAGUGAAUCACAAGUCCACGUAGAUUCAAGAGGAGAGAAUUAGGCUCCACCUCUUGAUGGGGGAGUGUCGAGGUUCUAGAAGAACUUGAGAUUGCAGUUUGCCACAAUAUCUCAGCCGCGGGAUCCCCGCAUCUUGCAGACAAAACCCAAAGUCUUGAUAAAAUGCCUGUGUGUCUGUUCUGUGCAGAUUCCUGAGGUGGGACCCCACACUGGGUUCCCACAACCUGUGGACUCAAUACAGGCAAUUCAGCAAACCAGCUCCCAACAUCUAUCCCUGAUUGCAGGGACAUUUAACAUAAAGCACAGCCUAGCACAGCAAAAGGCAGCUUCCCUGUCAUGGAGAAAGCAGAGAAUCUAGAGCUAGACCGGGUGGUUUCAAUCCUGGCUCUGUCACUUACUGUGUGACCUUGGGUAGGUGACUUAAACUCUCUGUGCCUCCGUUCCCUCAUCUGUAAAAGAUUUGGAUGAUAAAAAUAGUACCUAUGUACCUCCGUCAUGAGAAUCAAAUGGGUUACUGCUUGGAAGUGCCAAGGAUGGUAUAGAAAUAAAAUAAAACGUCCAUCAGCUCCUUCAGGCCCGGAAUGUGUGAUGGUGGGUGCUCCAGAUAUUCUACACAAGAGAAGGGCUCAGGGCAGGAGCAGAUGCUUCAGGCACCCGGGAAGACUGCGGCUGGUGGAGACCUGGGGAUACCGGGUUAUUUCUGCCUCCACACUGCAAGGACUCUCAUCUCUUAUGAGAAAGGCAAAUGACACCCAGCUGAGGCUGGGAAGUGCUGUAAUGUGGGUGGGGUGAUGGGGCUGGCUGCCAUGUCCAGGAUCUUCAUUGGACUGCUGUGUGGAGAGUCUACCCUUCCCUUGCCUUACUCUGUGUGUGUGUUUAAGUUCAUAACUUAUUCUUGCCUGUGGAUCUGGGAGAGUGAGGGACAGGGGCGGAUGGUAUAUUUAAUUAAAUAUCGCCACUCCCUCCUCUUUAAGGUCAUUACAGUCAAUAAGGGGGAGAAGAAAUAUCUCUUUAGGAGGCCUUUCAAAUGAAAAAAAAAUGAAUUACUGAAUGCAAAAACAGUCUUAUAUCUGUGGCAUCCUUCCUUCAGUUGUGAUUUAAUAUGUGCACGGUGCAAUACAGAAAUACAAAGCAGCUUGGGAAAAAGUCUCAGCCCUAAGAAUCUUAUAGUAUUAAAACUCGAGUAAUCCUACACAAGAGAAAAAUACAGCAAAGCCUGAGCUUGGCCCCUGCAAACCAGUGCACUCCACCCGCUGUGACCCGGGGGGUGGUGGGAGGCCUCUGGAGAGCGGCUGGGUGCUGCUUUUGACAGCUGAAUUUUAUUAACUGUUUUUUCAUUCCUCCUGACGGACCUGGCAAUGAACUCUUAUCAGUGUAUUGUGGCGAGUACAAGUCAAUUAAUUUCUUUUAAAUAACUUCAACUGAAAUUCUAUUUGAUUUAUAUUCCAAAAAAGAUUUCCAUUCCAUCAUUCCUUCCUGAGAUUAUGGUCCCGGCAGAGUUAAUCACACUGGCUACACAGUCACCCAUACCCCAGGGAGAAAACAGGAUCAAGGAGAGGAGGAAAUGAGACGGAGGUGGAGCUGAGAGCAUCCUAAAGACCCUUUAUUCAGUGUGAGGCCAUGUGCUCAGUGACAGGGGAGUUUGCUGAAAUCUUGCCCUCAGAAGAGCUUAUUUCUAGUGGUUAUGGCAGGGGAUGGAUUGGGGAGUGACAGGAAAUGUCUGGAAGAUGGGGGAGACUUAACCAAGAAGCAUGACUGGGGGCACCAGGGCCGCUGAGGUUUGCUGCUGAGCCACCUCCUCAUUUAGUAUCCAGUUUCUAGGGCUGGCAUCCCAGGACACCCUCCCUUAGCUCAGCCCCAGUUGUGAGCACCUGACCCUUCUAUGGCCUGCUGUGUGGGGCCACCCCAGCCAUGGUGGUGGUGAUGGUGAGCUGUCCCUGUGAGCAAGCCUCAACAGGCUUUGCUGUGGGUCUGUCCAUCCCUUAAACACAGGCUGGGACAAGCAGAGCUGCCCCCUUCCUGAGGGUCUGCCCACAGGGUCCCCCGAUUGUCACCAGCCAAGUCUUACAAACAAUAAGGCCUGGCUUAUCUGGGAGGGAGGGAGCAGGAGCUGGGUGGCACCUGGCCCAGAGAGCAGAGCUUAGUGAGUGGCUGGUGACAAUGACAAGAGGUUAGAGCUCCAGAGGGAGGGCGGCUCCUGCCCUAAGGGAGACAAGUGGUGGCUGGAUCCCAAGGCUGGGCAGGUGUAGGGCUGAGAGAGAUGCCUUCUCAAGCCAUCUCCUGCCCUAGUGACAGGCGGCCGAGUCAGGACUGGCAGGCUUCUGGGGGACAGCACGUCACUGCCCUGGGGUGGGAAUACUCUGGUGAAGAAUUCCAGGCAGUCAAACAGUUUGGCCAAUAUGAGUUUGGACAAAAAAAUAUAUAUUUGCAAAAUAUCUGCUGUGGAUGCUGUAUUAGUUUGCUAGGGCCACCAUAGCAAGGUAGCACAGACAGGGUGUGGCUUACAGAACAGAAAUGUAUUUUCUCACAAUCCUGGAGCUUAGAAGUCCAAGAUGAAGCUGUUGGCAGGGUUGCUUCCUUCUGAGGGCCCUCAGACCUCUGGCAUCAGAAGUUUCUAGGGCAUUUGAUAAAAAUGUGAACUUCUGAGACACUGAGUCAAAAUCUUUAGGAGUGUGGCCCAGGAUUUGACAUUUAAAUAAACUAAAUAAGCUCACCAGGUGACUCCCAGUGGUGCCCCCUGAAGUGCCAUCGCAUGGGUAAAUAAAGGGUACAGCACAGCCUCACCUUCAAGGAGCUCCCUAGUCAAGGAAUCAAGACCUGCACAAGACAAUCAGAGAAAGUGUCAUGCAGUAUAAUAAUCCAAUCACUGCCCAGUUGGAGGGCGCAGACCAAAAAGUGCCUCAGGAGCUUGGAGAAGGAAGAUGGGUCCCCAUGGAGCGGGGAGUGUUAGGGAAGCAGUCCCUGGAAGGUGGUGUUUCUCACGUCUUCCUCUGCACAGAGAUGAUUCGAGGCUGAGGGUUAGCUGUGUGUGAGGACAGGGAGGCUGGGAGAUAUGAGGAUCUGGAUAAAAACUUAUCUCAGCGUUGAGAGUAUCUUUGAGCAGUGUAUCCCUUUUGUCUUUAUCAAAACACAAAUUUUGUUUUUUCUGAAAUUCCUGUUUGCUGUCUGGGGAUGUGAUAUCGGUGCCUGACACAUCGUCACUUAACAAAGGUUUGUUUGCUGGCUUAAGAGUUUCAGAUGUUCUGUGUCGGUUCGUGGCUGCAGUGACUUUAUCUCUCAGGAGGGAGGUGUGUGGCUGGUGGGGGUGGUGGGGGAACCCAGCUGGUGAACAACACGUGCUGGUGGCGAGUUCUGACUCCAGCAGGUGAGAGUUGAUGUUGUUUUAAACAGUAUUCACCCCACCUGUCUUCCGAUACACAUAUUGAUCCCGGCCAACAAAGAGUUGACAGGAGACCACACAGAGAUAAAUAUGUCAGGGCUCUCGGUAGAAAACAACAUGCAUGGCGGUGACGGAACCCGCAGUGGAUGCAGCAGACUUUGGAACUGCACUUCCACUUACUGGCUGGGUGACCUCAGCAAAUGACCUAACUUCUCUGAGCCUCAGUUUCCUCGUCUUUAAGAUCAGGAUAAUAGGCCGGACGCGGUGGCUCACACCUGUAAUCCCAGCACUUUGGAAGGCCAAGGUGGGUGGAUCACCUGAGGUCGGGAGUUCAAGACCAGCCUGACGCACAUGGAGAAACUCUGUCUCUACUAAAAAUACAAAAUUAGCUGGGCAUGGUGGCAUAUCCCUGUAAUCCCAGCUACUUGGGAGGCUGAGGCAGGAGAGUUGCUUGAACCUGGGAGGUGGAGGUUGCUGUGAGCAGAGAUCGCGCCAUUGCACUCCAGCCUGGGCAACAAGACCACAAUUCUGUCUCAAAAAAAAAAAAAGAUUGGGAUGAUAAAAAUACCUAUCACAUUGUGAUAUGGCAAGGAUUAAGCUAAUUAUAAAAGAAGUUUAGAAUGAUAUCUGGAAUAUAAGUAUGCAAUAAAUGUUAGCGAUCAAUAUGGCUUUUUCCACCCAAAUGAGUGAUGUUCUGCGAAUUUACUUCAAACAAGAUAUCACGGCUGUUCUCUAAGGACUGGGUAGUCACUAACAAAUCCAUUUUCCUUAUCGUGAUCUAUAUAGCUCAGUGAUUUUUCUGCUCUCUGCUCCAAGCUAAGAACAGAGAGCUUCGCCUCCCAGACUGAAAUGAAGCAUCCGCUGGUACAGGACUGUGUAUGCGCCUCUGUCUGGAGGGGGCUGUCUGUUGGUUAAAGGGUGUCUUUUCCAGGCCCUGGAGAUUGCAGGCACUAACAGUCCACUCAGGUGACAACGUGUCGUACUUCUCUGUGCAUGCUGUGGGGACUCAGCCUCACACCAGGAUGUGUCCCUUCAAACCCAGUCCCUGGGGGCACACAGGCCGUGGGCUGUGGGAUGUGGCUCAGGAGGCUUGGGGAGUCCACUGUCAGCCAUCCUUGGCAUGCUUCACGCGUGGUGACCCCCAAGAGGGGAGAAGGCCACACCUCCUUAGAGCGUGGUGCUUCUCAAAGGGUCUCACUGUAGUUACCGUCUUGGAGUGGGUUCAUCCUUUUGCCUGCACUUUUAAGUCAUGGGGAAAUGUUAAAUUUGGGGAGGGUGGAAAAAGGGUCAGAGAGACAGAACUUGCUGACUCCUAUUUUGGGACUAGUUCUGCAAUCCAAUUUCUUUUUUCUUAAACAAUCUUAUAGAAAUCUGCCAGAGACAAUGAAUAAAGGCAGAACUCCCUGGUCGAAGCAGAGAUGCCUCUUUCUGGAGUCCCUGAAUUACCCAUAUGGGAUCUGAGGCUUCCUCUGAGCCAGUUUGAAAAUGCCUGCCCUCGGAAAUCCUCCUUGCCUUCUGAGCCACGCCCUCUGUCAGGGUGGGCAGGGUCCAGGAGAGAAGGGACCGCCGCUUCUGCUAGAACCAGGCAGGUUUCGUUUUGGAUGAUCAUUACCAAACUCUUGGCUCAAAUGCAUUGUUUAAACUUGACUUUUCUACAUUCUCCCAGGACCUGAGUACUAACUAAGGCCUGAGCAGGUAAGCUGAACCGCUUGACGUGAUAAUCCAAACUGACAGGAUUGUCAGCUGGUUACGAGUCUCCUCCUCCUUCCCACGUCACUCAGAGGACAGGAGGGCAGAGGGAGAGAUCGGAAGUGCUGGGCAUUAGGAUCGAGGAUGCGCUGGGUGCAGGACCCACCGAGGAGGUGUGGACUCUGGCAAGAGGGCCUAAAAACCCCAAAAGGCUCCAUCUAUAGACUUUCCACGUCAGCCUACAGCCACCCCAAAUUUUCUAUGAUUAUUAUUUUAACAACACAUAGGCCUUAUUUUUAAAAUCUGCUGCACUUGAGCAAUUUCAUCUGACGUCAGCUGGCUGCCGGCAACUCUGCUUGAAAACAAGAAUAACCAAAUCUUCUAAGGAGUAAUGCUGAACCUGCUUCAAACGCAAUAAAUCACAAAAACCAUUGUUUACAAUAAGUGGUAUCUGAUUGCUGUUAGAACCUGUGUUUAUUGCUUUUGUGCAUUAUGGUCUCUUGUAAUUUGGACAGCCAGAAAUUGUAUUCCUUUAUGCAGUGCGUAGGCAGGGUUUGUAAGGGGGGAGGCAUCUGUAAUUAUGCUGCCAGGGAGUGAGGUUGAGGAGCCUCCAAGGAGCAAGAAAAUGCAGUUGCCUGUUUUUCAUCUGAGGAGCUGGGCAUCAGGCUUCCCACUUUCCAGUUCUUGGAACCCUCAGGGCUCCAUUGGAGAGAGACCUGGGCAGGGGAGGAUAAGGAGUGGACCUUAGAGCUAUAGUGCCCCAGAUCAGAGAGCCCUUAAGUGGCCUCAGGGUGCAGAGUGCCAGGUGGGUGGGCAGACGCCGGCCCCACAGGAGGCUGGGCUUAUGGUUUUCCUGGAAAUUGCCUUGGUCUCUCCUGCACGUUUCUUCCUCAUUCUCCACCAUCCUGACGAGUGCCCUGACUGGACUUUGUAGGUGAAGGCUAGCAGCAGGGAUCUAGGAACAGCUGAUGACAGAAUUCUUUGGCACCUCUGUCUGCAAAUUUGAGAAGCAGCCACUUGACCAUGUGGCCUGGAUCUUGCCAUUGUCAGUCAGUAAAUGGAUGAUGUUGCUUGAUUUCUUUGAGGCACCGUUAGGAAGAAGGUCAGUGUGUCUGGGUGUGGUGAUCUGUCAUUCUCCUAAUUCAAAACCUCUGGACUCGAAGAAGAGGGUCUAGUUUCUCUUUCAUGAAAAUAGACCACGCUCCAUCUAUCCUUGCUGCUUUGGCUUCAGUUGGUUCUUCCACCCGGAAUGCUCUUUUCUGUCUAUUUCACCUGUGUGAAACCCACCCAUCCUUCCAGUUCCUGCACUUCCAUUAAUGACUUCCCUGAACUUGUCCCUCCUAUGUCCUUAAUCUCAGUAGAAUUUCACCACCAUUCCCCCAGCCUCUCAAGCCUAAAAACUAGGGUUCAUCUGAGACAUGUCUUUUUCCCUCCACCCAACACUAGCCCAGCACACAGAGACACUUGGGAACUGUUUGUUAAUGAAUUAAUGAACUUGAUAGUUAACCACCAACUCUAACCCAAAUCACUUUCUGGAUAUUUCUCCAAAUUGUCCCUCUUCGCAUUUCUACCACCACAGCCCAAGGGAGGGUCCUUAUUCAACAGGACCACCUCUGAACAGCCUGUAAAGCCCCCCAUAUCCCCCUGCACCCUAGGACCUGGUGUUCAGGGUCAUGUCUUAGCCUCUGACCCCCACUCCCACAACCUCUACUCCCCAACUUGCUCAUUUACUCCAAGUCCCUUCCGGUUCCUGAGCACAACAUACAUGCUAUUUCAUUACUAAGGAUGUUUCUCUGCCCAGAAUAUCCCUACCCCUUCUUCACCUGGCUUCCCCUCUUCAGAGACUUGGCUCAGGCACCACCUCCUCCAGGAAGUCUUUUCCAGCUGUGCCUGUGGGCCUUGGGGGGCCCCCGUCUCUACUUCCACAGCUCCUGUGUUUUUCUGUGUAGUAACUCUUGUCACAAUUAUAACAAACUGUAAAGGUCCACCCUUAAAGGCAGGAAUACUGUGUUAUCUGUCUGACCAUCCCCCAUGCCCAGCACAAUUCCUGGCCCACAGAAGGUCUCCUGUGAACGAGGAUCUAAAUGGAACUGGCACGAAUGCUCAAAUGGCACAUGAAGUGCAGAGAGCACCAAAUUGUAUUAAUACACAAUUGUUUGUUGACUUAGACCAAGUUCAUAGGCGGCUCCCCAAAGAAACCACAAGGACUAGAUCUGAGAAGUUGCAGCCCUCCACGGCAUCUGAGCAGAGUGGCUGUUCCUCUGUGGUGGCUCCAUGAGUGAGUUAGUGGGCACAGAAGGAGCCUGGUCUGCCGUGUUGAUUGAUAGCUGUCCCCACAAAGCAUGGGACUAGUCACGCAUGCUUUAUUAAAAAGAUAAAUGAAUCAAUUUUGUGAUUCUAAAGCUAUAGUCUAUUGGUCAAUUUGUACAAGCUCUGGCAUUAAUUAGAUGCUGAGCUGGACAGCAGGGUCCCCUCUCCCUCCUAGAGCUUAGAAGGGUUCUCUGAGGCUCCAGGACUUGAGUUUCAGUGAGAACUAUGGAUCCCUUCUGCCCUGCCCAGCCUGGCUGGCUGAGCAGUAAAGGAAGUGAGGAGAGAAGCUAAGGCAGGGCUCUACUUACAGAAGACCCUUGACUCUGGGGCCAUGGGCACCUGCUGGGCCCGGGACUGGGAAGGGCUGACCAGGAGCAACUAUUCGAAGGCAGCACCCUGCACACAGCCUAGCAUCUGCACUGCUCAAGGCCAAGGGUCAUGAUUUCCAGAUUCAUUUAUUUUAACAAACUUCCCCUUAAUACACACACGCGCACACACACGUGGGAAUGCUACACUAGCCAAGCUCGCCCCCAGCACCGAGAAACAAACUGGACGCACUCCUUUCUCUUCCUCUUCCCCUGCACACAGCAGACCCUCCAGGGACAAUGCACAUAAUUCAGGCUUUUGUGCCAUGGCGCAGCAAGCUAGGUUAUGAUUAUACCAGCCUCUGGGGUCUAGCCAGGUAGCCCCAUGGCCGUUGAUGGCUUUGUCUCUACAGGAAAAUACAUUUGGAGUUACAAACAGCUGACUUCUUGGCAGACUUCUUGGAAUUCAAGCAGCUCAUAGGCAAGGGGCUGGGAAGUGGACCCUCGAGCCGGUUGGCCAAUCAGCAGGUCCUCCAGGGCCCUCAUCCAUGCCUGCCCUGGCACUGGGGAGGCCACAGAGGAAUUAGUGAACAGAUCUCAGCUUACAAAGCCUCACAGUUUGAUCUGGGGUGAGGCAGGAGGCAGGAGGCAGGGAUUCCCUCCAGACCCUCAGAGCAGAACCAAGUCUUGCGUGUGGUGUCCCGCCAGCCCAUGUCUCUGAAGACAGGGGAGGCAGCGUGGGCUUUGUCAGGCUGGUGACGGACGUGCCUGGGAGCAAGAGCCUGGGUCCAGAACCUUCCUGUCACAGGGAAAGUGCAGAGCUCCCUGUUUGUCAGCUGCUUCGUGGUGCGGAGCCUGCAAAGUCCAGGGAGAGGUUUCGUGCAGAAAGCCCUGUCUCCCUGUGCCCGCUGUGGACGUGGAAGGCAGAGGCGCGUCCUCUCUCAGCCACUCUCCUCCAGCCCGGGGGUCUGCCGUCCGCUGAGCUCUUUUUUCUUUAAACUUAGGAACAGAAGCCAUUUGACAGAAACUUUUAAAAACAACCUAACUAGGCUGGGCGCGGUGGCUCACGCCUGUAAUCCCAGCACUUUGGGAGGCCGAGGCGGGUGGAUCAUGAGGUCAGGAAAUCGAGACCAUCCUGGCCAACAUGGUGAAACGCCGUCUCUACUAAAAAUAGAAAAAUUAGGUGGGCCUGGUGGCACGCACCUGUAGUCCCGGUUACUCAGGAGGCUGAGGUAGGAGAAUCGCUUGUACCGGGGAGGCAGAGGUUGCAGUGAGCCGAGAUCGUGCCACUGCACUACUCCAGCCUGCCGACAGAGCGAGACUCCGUCUCAAUAAAUAAAUAAAUAGAACCUAACUAAUAUAACAUUUGAAAUUUGGUCCUUUCCAGAAUCUUUUCCCAUCUUUUUAACAUGUGCAGAGUGGAUACAAGGCUGCCUCGUGUUUCCCAUUUUUCUCCUAAUGGAAUUCAUGUCUGGGUCUCCAUGUGUCGCCGGAGUCCACUCCCGCUGAAUGGAUGGCUGCCCAGGGUUCUCUGCUCCUAGGGCACAUUUGCUCAGCAGCUCCCUGUGGUAGAAAACUGGCUGGGCCCAUUCCCACCACUGGAAAGUCACUUUAGUGCAGUGUCUUCUUGCCUCUAAGAUACAUUGGCCUUCCAUUCUUUGAGCCUUGUGGGGUUAAUGAGAUGGAGAGUGAAGUAGGUAUUUUUGUUCUCCCUCAGACCCUCAUGGACAAGUCAUGUUUUACCUCUGUGCUUCAGUGUUCUCCUCUUCAAAACAGGGAGGAUGAGAAGUCCCCUUUCCCAGAGGACUAUGAAGAUUAAAUGAGAUAGUGUGUAGCUCAUCAUAAAUGCUCAAGAAAGGGGAGCAUAGAAGUAAUAAUUAGAGUAACCCCCUGAAUUAUCCUUGUUCUGGGAAAGCAGACAAGUCCGGUGGGCUGGGGGCCAACUUCCUCAGCCCCUCCGUGGGGACCCAGCCCGGAGGGAACCUGAGACUUGGCCUAUGGCUCCUCCUCCCACAUGACCCUGACGCUGUAAAUGUCGCCUAACAGUCUUAAGCAGUUUUCACUGUGACCUGUUGUUAUUUUCCUUGCUUAGAAGUAAAGAUGUAAGCGUUGGAGCCUACCCGUUGACUCGUGAGAGAACCCAGUGGUCCUCUGGGAGGGCAAGUGUUUGAGCCACUGGGGAUUAGGGAGCAAGAGCCUGGCUGCAAAGAGAGGGGGGAUCUUCCCUUCUCCAGGAGAUGCUCACGGAUCUCAGGCCCUCGCUUUCCUCUGUCUGCUGAGCCCCAUUUGGGCCUCUGCCUCUGCUACUUCCGUGGCCUAGAAAAGACAGCCCUAGAAAAGAAACCCCAGCUGUCCCCUCCGGGAAGGCUCUGUGCACCUUCUCCAUGCUGGUGUGGGCGCUGUAGCACUCCCUGGCCAGUACCCAGGACACCUGAGCUCCCCACCAGCUUCCACACGCAGCAAGCACCGCAUGUGCUUGCUCCCCACUGGGCCUGGUCCACAGCUGCACACGCCAACACAUGCACCUGGUCCAGGGCCCCAGCCAUCCCCUGCCCUCCACAGUCACUCCUAGGUCUGAGCCACCCCACAGCUGUCCCUUUCCUUUCUCCUAUCCCCAUAUCAUGAACUGGGUGACCAUCCUCCAAGAGAGUGGCUCCAGAUGUCCUGAGCAGGCAUCAGAAGCAGCCAAAGUGUUCAGUCUCCUCUGCUUUCUCGGAAAAAUGUUUUCUUUUUAUUAGUGACUUCCCCCAGGCAAUCCUUAACCCAGGGAAAGAGGCUGCUCUGUGGGCCUAGUGAGGGCUGGGCUGCCAGGCGGCAUGUGGAGAGCCCACUUCUCUCCUCUCUGGGAGUCCUGCACAGACCAUGCCCUGGAAUGCACUUUCCAGUCUCAAGGCUUUUCUCAUGUUCUGUGGGGUCUGUGCCCAGAGGCUAUGUCAGAAGCUGCAGCCACCAAGCGGGGACAGCCUCCCUAGGUAAACUGACACUGACCCUCCGCUAGUCAGUCUUGGACCCGUCCACUACCCCGUCAUCCACCCAUGACUUCUUCCAGCCAGAUCCAGCUCCUAUGUUGUCAGCCUUGGCAAUACCCCAGGGUCCCAGGUCCCCCGUCCUCCCCUCCCCCCCAGGCUCCCUCCCACCCAGGCAUUCUGACCUGCUAGCUCAGACCCAGAAUCCUGCCUCCCAUGGCAUCCGAUGACUCCCCCUGGCCAGUGUGCCAAGGCCUCUAGACAGCUGCUGCCACACCCUCCAACUCUGGCCAGCCCCGCAGCAGAAUGAGGCUUGGGCCCAGGACCAGGGUGUUGCCCUAUUUAGGAGCUGUCAGCAGAGGGAGUGUUGGCAUAAACCACCCUGGGGUAUGUGAACCCAGAAAAUCUGAGACAGGUCUCGGUGAAUUUAGAAAGUUUAUUUUGCCAAGUUGAGGACUCGCCUGUGACACAGCCUCAGGAAGUCCUGACGACAUGUUCCCAAGGUGGUCGGGGGACAGCUUGGUUUCAUCCAUUUUAGGGAGACAUGAGACAUCAAUCAAUAUAUGUAAGAAGUAUAUCGGUUCUGUCUGGAAAGGUGGGACAACUUGAAGCAAAGGCAGGAAGACCCAAAGUGAGGAGGGAGCUUCCAGGUCCCAGAUAGGUGAGACACAAAGAUUGCAUUGUUUUGAGUUUCUGAUUAGCCUUUCCAAAGGAGGCAAUCAGAUAUGAAUCUAUCUCAGUGGGCAGAGGAACUUUUAUUAAUGAACUUGAUUUUAUUAAUGAACAAAUUUAUUUUGAAUAGAAUGGGAGGCUGGUUUGCCCUAAGCAAUUUCCAGCUUGAGUUUUCCUUAGAGAUUUUGGAGGCCCCAAGAUAUUUUCCUUUCACUGGUAUCAUCCACCCAGGAGAGAAGCCAGGUCAGGGAGUGGCAGAGAGAGGAGGACGGGUCUGAAGACUUCCUAGUCUCAUUGAAGGUGGUCAGUGACCACCCCAGGUGAGGGUGAAGCCCUCUGCUAAAUAGAAAGCAGCCCAGACAAGGCCAAAUCCACCUCAAAACGGGGUACAGGGCAGGGGUGUUCAUCGUGUUAAUUCUGUUGGGCUUGGCCUCUGCGCUUUCAUGGGCUCAGAUACCUAAGCCUUCCAGGGCCUCAGGUGCCUGAUCUGCACCCAGGGAGGGCUGGAGGGAAAGGAGCCUGAAGGGGCUUUCAGGGCCUUCUGUGAUUCGUUGACUACUUCAAACAAAAACAAAGCCUUCCCAGCCGGGGUGAUGGAGGAAAAUAAGAACAAAGCUGGCUGUGUUUGCUUGUGUUGGAAUCCAAGGAGGGGACCUACUGGAAUUUCCCUCCCUUUGCUGGAGGCCAAGGUCAGGCCACUGCCCUGACCUCUGUUUCCUGGGCCCUGAGAUCAUGGCACUGUCAGAGCCCACUGGGAAGGACAGGCGCAGGUGAUUAUUUAUACAAGUCUUUUCUUUCAGUGGACUAUUUACGUACUCCCAACACUUUAAGGAAAGAAACUUUGGUUUCACAGUGGAUGAAAGUUUUCCCAUGCUUUAAGGUGACUCUUUCAUACAUUUCUUCUUAGUACAACACAAAUCUCAUUAUAGGAAUUUCAGUAUUUUAACAAAAGGAACCACAGUCAUCGUAAUGAGAUCCCCGAAUAAAGUUCAGUUCAUUUUCAUCUGUCUUUUCUCCCCAAAUAUUAUUGCUAGAAAUGUUACAUUAUCAUAAACCCGAGUUCAGGAUGCAUAGUUUCCACAAUUGUCUUCUUUCCUCCAUAUACAAAUUCUGAUUACUGCUUUCAUUUUACAAAGACCACCCCCCCCCCCGCUCCCCCUCAGGGGUGUUUCCAUCUUCUCAGAUAUUUUUCUUUGCCUUACCCCAAGCUACGUACAUAACCGGAUGGCUAGAAUUAGGAGAGUCGAUGGUGGAUAUUCCUGUAUCCGUCUAUCUGCCCCCUGCCUGCCAUGUGGUGUGGGAUACAUGCAGGAGGUAUCCUGGGAGGGGACUGCUUCGAGGGGCUUCCCCAAGGGCAUUCCUUGUGGCCAUGCAGAAGGCCAUGCAGAAGGACUCCCAGGGAAGGCUGUGGCCCAAGCCCUCCUAGCCAGCUCUGCCUGCAGGAGGAAGGACAAGGGACUCCUACAUGGCACCCUUGGAGGCGAGGUUCGUGCACUGGAAGUUUCCAAGCAGACUUUAUUUCCACUCAGCCAUGUCAGAAACCUCUAGCAGGACUGGUGCUCUAACUUCACACAGGGUUUCAGAGUCAGGGCCUUCUCCCUAGUACAGUGAAGCUGCAGGUGCAGCCUGUCCCCUAGGUCCAUGUGCUGCAUUGGGCCAGCUGGGCAGUCAUGAGCUCCCUCAGCAUCCUCAGGCCCAGUAGCCACUCCUCUCUGCCUCCUCCCUGGUGUCUAUUGAUGUCUCUGCAGGGAACAUGCUCCAGGUGACCCAGACACUGAGCACUUUGCAGGCAGGCAGCAUCCUCCCCAUAGCUAAGAGUAGUAACUACCUGUACCCCAUUUCUUGGGAGGAAACAGAGGCUCAGUUUCAGCACGUUGUUCAAUAGACUGCAGCCAGAUGGUAAACAUCAGAGCCAGGACGUAAGGCUCUGUUGAAUUCCAAAGCCCACACUCUUAAGCAGUCUGUGGUCUUAGUAGUAUCAUUAAUUAUGCAAUGAUGCAUCAAUACUCAGGGGUCCCGUAGAGGUAGUUGGGACGUUUAUCCCUGAACUAAAUGGUCAAAGCUCACUAUGCUUACUAAGUUUGUGCACCUGCUUUUCACAGCCUUUCUGCAUCUCCCCUUAUUCUCAUUAGUUAAACUUGCCAUGGUCAUUGUUUUUGCCUAAAGCACUAGUACCCACCUGACCUGCUGUGGACCUGCUUGUUAGAAUUGUUUGCAAAGGAAGCAUCCAUAGGCUAUGAACAAGGAUGCUGGGGCUUGCCUGUGAACACCAAGCUUCAGUGUGUGUUUAUUCUAAGGCUUUUUUUUUUCUUUUGAGAUGGAGUCUAGCUCUGUUGCCCAGGCUGGAGUGCAGUGGCAUGAUCUUGGCUCAUGGCAACCUCCCCACCUCCCAGGUUCAAGCAAUUCUCCCACCUCAGUCUCUGAGUAGUUGGGACUAUAGGCGUGUACCAUCACGCCUGGCUAAUUUUUGUAUUUUUAGUAGAGAUGGGGUUCCACCAUGUUGGCCAGGCUGGUCUCGAACUCCUGACCUCAAGUGAUCCACCUGCCUCAGCCUCCCAAAGUGCUGGGAUUACAGGUGUGAGCCACCACACCCAGCCUCUAAGGCCCUUUUGAUUGCUUUUUGAAUUUUGGUUAUGUUUGGGAUCACAGAAGGAUGCUUGUUCUUAUUUCUGGGCAGAUGGAAGACCUUUUACCUUUUUGAAAUCUGAUCAGAAAAAAAAAAAAGCUUUUUGCAGGUUGGAGAGUCAUCAGGUGGGGUGGGAAGGUGAGGCGGGUCUUUUGGGUUCUCUUCCCACAAAGUAGGCUGGUAGCCUUGAGUAUGAGUGGGGAAACCCAUGGCUCAGUCUCUGGAGAGAGAGUUUCUUCUCCUCCAACCCAAGCCCUGAGUCUGGACCCCCGAGCUUUUAUUCCUGACUCCAGUGGCAACUCUCUCUAAAGCCAUCUACCACCUCCAGGCCAGGCUGUUGGACGUGCAGCUCUUCCCCUGCUGCCGCCACAGAGUUUACAGAGUAAGCCCAGCCCUGCAGAGGUGACCAGUGCUGUGCAGAUGUGAGGACCUGCAUGGACUCGACUUUGUCAGUGCCCUGAUUGCGUUCCCUGUGGAGCUGACCACGAGAGCAGGUGUUAGAGCCGUCUCUGAAGAACUGAAUGUUAGAAUCUAUGCGCCUGCCUGUGGGGGUGGUUACGGGCAUUUAGUGGGGAGGGGGGAUGGUUCUCAGAACCUUGGGGGGCAGAGGCAUUCAGAACUGCCUGGCAUUCUCACUUCCACUGGUUUCUUUACCAGCACCAGUGUGCAUUUUGUUCAGCAAACCCGGAACUCAGGAAGCUUUGCCACCUGGGUGCCUGUCAGCGGCAGCACGGUCCACCCCAGGGUGGGCUGGGGCAGAGGGCCUGCAUGCCACAGCGAGAGCAGAAAGGGAGCAGAGCCAUUUUGUAGAGCGAGUUUUCCAACCCCUCUUAUGAUCCUUCCUCUAUUCUAAAGCAAAGGACAUAAAUACUAAACGGUGGUUCUUGCCAGUGCUGAUAAGGAAAACCAGUAAAUGCAGGAGUCUCAUUAAGAAAAUCCUAAAAUUUUAGUCUUAUCACUGCUGCAACAUAAUACAGUAAGUAUGUUAAUUCUAACCUCCCUUAGCUUCCCCCCGCCAAAAUCCCUUUCAGCUAAGGCUGGCAGGAAUGAACUGCACUCUGGCUACAGACUGAAGCCACGUCUGAUUUGGAUUUUUUUCCUCGCCUUGGCUUCACGUAGUGAGUCUCCUAUUUGGGUGGACAUGGCUUUUACCCCCUCAUACUUCCCAGCUGCCUUUGCCAUUAUUCAGUUCAACAAACAUUGAGGAAGUACCUACUGUGUGCAGGCCACAGUCGUAGGAGCUGGGAAAUGUCAGAGUCAGCUGAGUUCAUCUCUUUGCAAGAGCCAAUAAGCCGACGAGGGAGCAAUGAUUUAUAGGCCAAGCCUGCCAGCCGGCCUUGUCCCCAGCAAAGACUCAUUUCAACAAGCUUCUCUUCCAAGUGAUUAUUUGCUGUUUGUACUGCUUGGACUUGGCACGCUUCUACAAUUCCUUUUACCAAAGAGGAAAGAGGGACCUUGAAGUCCGGGCUCUGUUUCCCUGUGAGAAGCCGCCUCGGCCCACCGAGAUGUCCCGGCACCAUAGCCGCUUCGAAAGAGAUUACCGGGUGGGCUGGGACCGCCGCGAAUGGAGCGUCAACGGGACGCAUGGGACCACCAGCAUCUGCAGUGUCACCUCGGGGGCCGGUGGCGGCACAGCCAGCAGCCUCAGCGUCCGGCCCGGCCUCCUGCCGCUGCCCGUGGUGCCCUCCCGGCUGCCCACCCCGGCUACAGCUCCUGCUCCCUGCACCACCGGCAGCAGCGAGGCCAUCACCAGCCUCGUGGCCAGCUCUGCGUCUGCGGUCACCACCAAGGCUCCCGGCAUCUCCAAAGGGGACAGUCAGUCCCAGGGACUGGCGACCAGCAUCCGGUGGGGGCAGACGCCUAUCAAUCAGUCCACACCCUGGGACACUGAUGAGCCACCCUCCAAACAGAUGAGAGAGAGUGACAAUCCAGGCACAGGGCCAUGGGUGACCACGGUGGCCGCCGGGAACCAGCCCACCCUGAUUGCACACUCCUAUGGAGUGGCCCAGCCUCCCACCUUCAGCCCGGCUGUGAACGUCCAGGCCCCGGUCAUUGGGGUGACCCCCUCACUGCCUCCCCACGUGGGGCCCCAGCUCCCGCUGAUGCCAGGCCACUACUCGCUCCCUCAGCCGCCCUCUCAGCCACUGAGCAGCGUGGUGGUCAACAUGCCUGCCCAGGCCCUGUAUGCCAGCCCUCAGCCCCUGGCCGUGUCCACACUGCCCGGUGUGGGGCAGGUGGCCCGCCCAGGACCCACCGCUGUGGGCAACGGCCACAUGGCAGGGCCCCUGCUGCCUCCACCGCCGCCAGCCCAGCCGUCCGCCACUCUCCCCAGUGGUGCCCCUGCCACCAAUGGGCCCCCCACAACCGACUCGGCCCACGGGCUGCAGAUGCUGCGGACCAUUGGCGUGGGGAAGUAUGAGUUCACCGACCCGGGGCACCCCAGAGAAAUGUUGAAGGAAUUGAACCAGCAACGCAGAGCGAAAGCGUUUACAGACCUGAAAAUUGUUGUUGAAGGCAGAGAGUUUGAAGUCCACCAAAAUGUUCUAGCUUCCUGCAGCUUGUAUUUCAAGGACCUGAUUCAAAGGUCCGUGCAAGACAGCGGCCAGGGCGGCCGGGAGAAGCUGGAGCUCGUCCUGUCGAACCUGCAGGCAGACGUCCUGGAGUUGCUGCUGGAGUUUGUCUACACGGGCUCCCUGGUCAUCGACUCGGCCAACGCCAAGACACUGCUGGAGGCGGCCAGCAAGUUCCAGUUCCACACCUUCUGCAAAGUCUGCGUGUCCUUUCUCGAGAAGCAGCUGACGGCCAGCAACUGCCUGGGCGUGCUGGCCAUGGCCGAGGCCAUGCAGUGCAGCGAGCUCUACCACAUGGCCAAGGCCUUCGCGCUGCAGAUCUUCCCCGAGGUGGCCGCCCAGGAGGAGAUCCUCAGCAUCUCCAAGGACGACUUCAUCGCCUACGUCUCCAACGACAGCCUCAACACCAAGGCUGAGGAGCUGGUGUACGAGACAGUCAUCAAGUGGAUCAAGAAGGACCCCGCGACACGCACACAGUACGCGGCUGAGCUCCUGGCCGUGGUCCGCCUCCCCUUCAUCCACCCCAGCUACCUGCUCAAUGUGGUUGACAAUGAAGAGCUGAUCAAGUCAUCAGAAGCCUGCCGGGACCUGGUGAACGAGGCCAAACGCUACCAUAUGCUGCCCCACGCCCGCCAGGAGAUGCAGACGCCCCGAACCCGGCCGCGCCUCUCUGCAGGUGUGGCUGAGGUCAUCGUCUUGGUUGGGGGCCGUCAGAUGGUGGGGAUGACCCAGCGCUCGCUGGUGGCCGUCACCUGCUGGAACCCGCAGAACAACAAGUGGUACCCCUUGGCCUCGCUGCCCUUCUAUGACCGCGAGUUCUUCAGUGUAGUGAGUGCAGGGGACAACAUCUACCUCUCAGGUGGGAUGGAAUCAGGGGUGACGCUGGCUGAUGUCUGGUGCUACAUGUCCCUGCUUGAUAACUGGAACCUCGUCUCCAGAAUGACAGUCCCCCGCUGUCGGCACAAUAGCCUCGUCUACGAUGGGAAGAUUUACACCCUCGGGGGACUUGGCGUGGCAGGCAACGUGGACCACGUGGAGAGGUACGACACCAUCACCAACCAAUGGGAGGCGGUGGCCCCUCUGCCCAAGGCAGUACACUCUGCUGCAGCCACAGUGUGUGGCGGCAAGAUCUACGUGUUUGGUGGGGUGAACGAGGCAGGCCGAGCUGCCGGCGUCCUCCAGUCUUACGUUCCUCAGACCAACACGUGGAGCUUCAUCGAGUCCCCAAUGAUUGACAACAAGUAUGCCCCCGCUGUCACGCUCAAUGGCUUCGUUUUCAUCCUGGGCGGGGCUUAUGCCAGAGCUACCACCAUCUACGACCCUGAGAAAGGAAACAUUAAGGCGGGCCCAAACAUGAACCACUCUCGCCAGUUCUGCAGUGCUGUGGUGCUUGAUGGCAAGAUUUAUGCAACUGGAGGUAUUGUCAGCAGUGAAGGGCCCGCGCUGGGCAACAUGGAGGCCUACGAGCCCACAACCAACACAUGGACCCUCCUCCCCCACAUGCCCUGCCCUGUGUUCAGACACGGCUGCGUCGUGAUAAAGAAAUAUAUUCAAAGCGGCUGACAUCAGCAGAAAGCCCACGAUAAGACUGUGGACAAGUCUGGUGAGGCAAGUGCCACGCAAUGAUAAUUUUCCAGCGACACCAACAAGAGGCCAACAAAACACAAUCAAGGAACUCACUGCGCUCAACAUGUUGAAUAUUCUCUACAUUGAAUGUAGAAAAUCAUCCUCGCCUUUGGAUGAAACGGAGGCACCGCGCUUGGAGCCGCAGGAACCACGAUCCCGCCAUGGGGCUGGCUGCCUCCUGAACAGGGGCGCUCGCUCUGCCAGGUGCAAUAGAGUUUCACGUAUUUUUCAACUGGGAGAGAGAAGCUGUUUUUUCCUUCCUGCAGAGCAAGCUUGAUCCCUAAACAACCAUAGAUCAGUUAUCUUAUGACAACAUUAGGCAUCAGGCUCUCUUGGAAUAAGAUCAAAGUGUCCUUAUCACUUUGAUUCCUACUUUUGUUUUUUAACCGAUCUACACUUUCAGUGGCCGACAGAAAACGAGGGACAAUACUGUGCAUCACAAGGCCUAGGAGGCUGCUGGUCCCCACUGGGGCUGAAGAGAAGCCCAGCUGCCCACGCGGAGCCAGGGGUGGCAGCUGUGGGACAGCCGGGGAGCAGGGACAGCGGUCUGUCCUUCACAGGUUUUUCUACUGUGUUUUUGCUGGAGAAGGACAGUGAUUGCGCUAGCUUUCUCUUACCCGGUAUGAAUUAUUUAGAUUUCUGAGGCAUUUUCUUGAUAAACAAAAGGCUAUUUUUAAGUACUGAGAGGAGGAGCAGGCCACAAGAGGGAUAAUGUUGUGGGAAUUCCCAAAGCUCUUUGUAGGUAGUGCCAGAGGGGGGCUUUUGCUCUCAUUUUUCUAUGUGCAGAAUAGAGGAUCUCUCCUGGGGUGGGCGAUGCCCCCAUUUUAUUUUUAGAAAAAGUAACUCCCAGACAGCCCCAUAAAAGCUGUGCCCAAGGAAGAAGAGUCUGCUCUAGAAGGAGCCCGGUUCUGGCUCAGGACACCGGCCCAGCUCCCUCCAUGAGGUCAAGCUGAGGACCAGGCCAGUGGGAAGGGAAGGAGGGAGAAUUAGCGUCUAUAAAGCACAGGAGACUAUUUUUGAUAUUCAUAGCUAUAUAUUAAGGCACCUGCCACAAGAGCUCUCAGGAUGGGGACAGCCUUCUUAGUGGAGCCAUGGCAGCAAGGCCUGAGGGCAUGAACAGAACCACUCUUCUUGUCACAUACGAACCUGAGAAAAGGGAAGCCAGGAGGGAGGUCACACCAUGGCUCAAAAGGGAAAGGCCUUCCCACUUGUCCUUAGCCCCUCAAACCUCACACGGUCAACAGUUUCCAUUCCAGGGCAGGAGAAUGCUGCCGCCACUGCGCUGUUGAGUUGAAGUUGGUACCAAAUACACAUUUACCACUUUUAUAUCUGGGAAGUCAACUUGCCAUCGUUUCAUGAUAACAACCAUUUAUAAGAGAAAAAGACAGGACACGCUUUCCAUCGUUCAGUAUUUGAUGACACAAAAUUCCAGUUCUAACGUUGGGCAUCAACUUCUAGCACUACGAGUGUGGCUCCCACUUGGACAAGAUACCGAGCUUCGUUAUGCAGUUUUUAAUAUUAUUUAUUAUUUUAAAAAGUAAUAAGCACAAAACUACAUACAUUGUAUGUCAUUUAAAGUAUUUAUGUCAAACAGGGUGCAAGUGUGAACCCAAGGACUGGAGCACAAAUUCCUAACUGCCUGGGGCAGGGCUAAUGUUAGCAUUGGUGUGCGUCUGCCUCCAAAGGAGGUUCUAGUUGUCAGCGAGACUCAACACAGAUGACAUUGAAAUUCGUUUCUCUCCUCAUCUAUCACACUGGAGCAAAACUGGCUAUUUCUGUGAAUGAUAUAAAACAGGGUUCUCUGUAAUGGUAUUGUACAUAGUAUAUGUUUACUGUUAAGUUCUUGUUAUAUUAUAAUAAAUAUAUUUAUAGAUCUAGA